CUUCCUCUCGCCGUCUCACAGUCGCUCUGCAGCCUCCGGCGACUGGGGGGAUGUGAGGCCGGCGCCCCAGCCCCCCGCCCCGCCAUGAGCCCCCCGCUCUGAGGGCCCCGGCCCCUGGAUGCACAGCCCCGGCGCUGGUUGGAAGUGAGCCAUCAGAGCCUCUGGAGCCGUGCUUGUGAACUCCCUGGAUGCAGGUGGAGGCCCUGGGCUGACCAAUGGCUAAGGGUUGGAGCUGAAUUGCCAGCCUCUCACUUGGCAUGGAAGAUGGCAGUCUCCUCCCCUUAAGCAGCCCCAAAGGUUGGCAGAGGGGAGAGCAGAAGGGGGAGCUGCACAAGGCCAAGAUCAAAGCCACUCCCUUGCUUGGGGAGCACCCUUUUUCUUCCAUGGGGCUGAGUCCAGGGCCCUGUGGCCAUACUGAAUGUUGAGAAGGAGGCAGCAUCUCCCCAGGAGCUCUCCUGUUUCACCUUCCUCCCACCUCCUUCCCUUCUCCGCCAUCUCCCCAGUUGGGGAACUACUGUGCCAAGUCCCUUCCCUCUGGUCUAGCCUGCUGCCUCUGUGGCCACUUUACUUUACUUGGCUCAGGAAUCACCAAAGAGAGGGGGUCAAGGCCUAGAGGGGACCUGGGCCCUGGAAGAGAGGACAGAACCAGAAAGGAAGGCUGGGGUUGGGACCAGAGAGGACAGGGCUCAAGGGAGGAUGGAGGCUGGGACAGGAGAGGCACACGGGAAAAACCUGAGCCCAGAUGGCCCUUUGGCUGGGCUCUCCAGAGUCUCUCCUGGGCCCUUGGAAUCUGCUGCCCAAACUGGGGGAGACUCUGAGACCAGAGGGCCAGAUGGGGCUGAUUCAAGACACGGGCUCUACAUCAGCUGGGAGGAAAUGCCCCUGUCUGGUCCACCUGCAGCUCUACGCUUCACCCCUCUCAGGAGGUUAACUUUCACAUCAGCAACUUGGGUGUCAGGUUCCGGCUCUAGGCCAGCAGGCCUCAGCCCCUCUCACCUCCAACCUCUUCUCCCAGGAAGGUUUUUCUGGGGACCCAGAGCUUCAGGCUGCAGGAAGGUGUUGCCUGGCCCUUGCCUUAGAUUAUUGAGUGUCAAAGGAGCCCUGACUCCAGGUCCGCUUUUCCCCCUGCACACUGCCAAGGCUGCCUUCCACCCUGGGCCUCUCUGGAGGCUGCUCAGUGCUCUUCCCGACUCCCAGGCCUUCCCGCCCAAGCUCCACAGCCCCCACAGCAGGAUGGGGAGGGGACUUCUCCUCGUCAGGAAGGCCCUGGGCUAAGCUCACCAUCCCCACCCUGUCUCCGCACCACUUCCUUUUUCCUCCAUCUUGCCUGCAGGGAUUGUAAACCCUGGUGGUCAGAAGCUUUGGGCCUAUAGGGUCAGCCUCUCACCCUGGGGAUCCGUAGGGGAACUCCAAUCCCCUUCAGUUCAGCUUCCUCCCUGCAGGACCCAUUCCAAGGAGCCUAGCUCUGGCUCCUGAGGUGACCCCAGCCCAGAAGUCCCAUUCCCCUCUACCCCAACCCCCAGAAUGGCAGGAGGAGCAGGGCAGUCUGGGAGUGACAGGUUCGGAAAGAGUCUGGGGUGGGGGAAUUCGGCGAUUGGGCUGUAACCGUCUUGUUUUGCUUGCCCCACAAACCUGCACGUCCGGGACGUCCGCUGCGCCCUCCCAGGCGCGUUCAGGUUAUAGAACUGCUCUCAGAAUGACAGGCUGGUGGCACCCGGCUGGGGCGGGGGGUGGGGAGGUGAAGGGGGGAGCCCCAGGCAAGGGGGAGCUGGAGGGUUAAAAAUAGCAGCAGCCUUGUUUCGGUUAGCAAAUGUGGAGGCGGGGAGCUGGAGGCGGGGCGGGCGGCGGACGAUGUUUGCCCGCAGCGCAGGGCUGUGCUUCCCCUGGGUCCCGGGAGUGAGUCACGGCGGAGACGCUGAGGAGGUGCUGGCGCAGCACCCCACCCCCACCGGGCGAGGGGCUGAGCGCAGGCCUCGCCCCCCAGAUUCCAGCGCUGAAGGAGAUGGGACCCAGGUGAGCCCGGGUGCCCACUACUGCAGCCCCACUGGCGCAGGCUGCCCCAGGCCCUGUGCAGACACACCAGGCCCUCAGCCGCAGCCCAUGGACCUGCGGGUGGGCCAGCGGCCCCCAGUGGAGCCCCCACCAGAGCCCACAUUGCUGGCCCUGCAGCGUCCCCAGCGCCUGCACCACCACCUCUUCCUAGCAGGCCUGCAGCAGCAGCGCUCGGUGGAGCCCAUGAGGCUCUCCAUGGACACGCCGAUGCCCGAGUUGCAGGUGGGACCCCAGGAACAAGAGCUGCGGCAGCUUCUCCACAAGGACAAGAGCAAGCGAAGUGCUGUAGCCAGCAGCGUGGUCAAGCAGAAGCUAGCGGAGGUGAUUCUGAAAAAACAGCAGGCGGCCCUAGAAAGAACAGUCCAUCCCAACAGCCCCGGCAUUCCCUACAGAACCCUGGAGCCCCUGGAGACGGAAGGAGCCACCCGCUCCAUGCUCAGCAGCUUUUUGCCUCCUGUUCCCAGCCUGCCCAGUGACCCCCCAGAGCACUUCCCUCUGCGCAAGACAGUCUCUGAGCCCAACCUGAAGCUGCGCUAUAAGCCCAAGAAGUCCCUGGAGCGGAGGAAGAAUCCACUGCUCCGAAAGGAGAGUGCGCCCCCCAGCCUCCGGCGGCGGCCCGCAGAGACCCUCGGAGACUCCUCCCCAAGUAGUAGCAGCACGCCCGCAUCAGGGUGCAGCUCCCCCAAUGACAGCGAGCACGGCCCCAAUCCCAUCCUGGGCUCGGAGGCGCUCUUGGGCCAGCGGCUGCGGCUGCAGGAGACUUCUGUGGCCCCGUUCGCCUUGCCGACAGUGUCCUUGCUGCCCGCAAUCACUCUGGGGCUGCCCGCCCCUGCCAGGGCUGACAGUGACCGCAGGACCCAUCCGACUCUGGGCCCUCGGGGGCCAAUCCUGGGGAGCCCCCACACUCCCCUCUUCCUGCCCCAUGGCUUGGAGCCCGAGGCUGGGGGCACCUUGCCCUCUCGCCUGCAGCCCAUUCUCCUCCUGGACCCCUCAGGCUCUCAUGCCCCGCUGCUGACUGUGCCCGGGCUUGGGCCCUUGCCCUUCCACUUUGCCCAGUCCUUAAUGACCACCGAGCGGCUCUCUGGGUCAGGCCUCCACUGGCCACUGAGCCGGACUCGCUCAGAGCCCCUGCCCCCCAGUGCCACCGCUCCCCCACCGCCGGGCCCCAUGCAGCCCCGCCUGGAGCAGCUCAAAACUCACGUCCAGGUGAUCAAGAGGUCAGCCAAGCCGAGUGAGAAGCCCCGGCUGCGGCAGAUACCCUCGGCUGAAGACCUGGAGACAGAUGGCGGGGGACCGGGCCAGGUGGUGGACGAUGGCCUGGAGCACAGGGAGCUGGGCCAUGGGCAGCCUGAGGCCAGAGGCCCCGCUCCUCUCCAGCAGCACCCUCAGGUGUUGCUCUGGGAACAGCAGCGACUGGCUGGGCGGCUCCCCCGGGGCAGCACCGGGGACACUGUGCUGCUUCCUCUGGCCCAGGGUGGGCACCGGCCUCUGUCCCGGGCUCAGUCUUCCCCAGCCGCACCUGCCUCACUGUCAGCCCCAGAGCCUGCCAGCCAGGCCCGAGUCCUCUCCAGCUCAGAGACCCCUGCCAGGACCCUGCCCUUCACCACAGGGCUGAUCUAUGACUCGGUCAUGCUGAAGCACCAGUGCUCCUGCGGUGACAACAGCAGGCACCCGGAGCACGCCGGCCGCAUCCAGAGCAUCUGGUCCCGGCUGCAGGAGCGGGGGCUCCGGAGCCAGUGUGAGUGUCUCCGAGGCCGGAAGGCCUCCCUGGAAGAGCUGCAGUCGGUCCACUCUGAGCGGCACGUGCUCCUCUACGGCACCAACCCGCUCAGCCGCCUCAAACUGGACAACGGGAAGCUGGCAGGGCUCCUGGCACAGCGGAUGUUUGUGAUGCUGCCCUGUGGUGGGGUUGGGGUGGACACUGACACCAUCUGGAAUGAGCUUCAUUCCUCCAAUGCAGCCCGCUGGGCCGCUGGCAGUGUCACUGACCUCGCCUUCAAAGUGGCUUCUCGUGAGCUAAAGAAUGGUUUCGCUGUGGUGCGGCCCCCAGGACACCAUGCAGAUCAUUCAACAGCCAUGGGCUUCUGCUUCUUCAACUCAGUGGCCAUCGCCUGCCGGCAGCUGCAACAGCAGAGCAAGGCCAGCAAGAUCCUCAUUGUAGACUGGGACGUGCACCAUGGCAACGGCACCCAGCAAACCUUCUACCAAGACCCCAGUGUGCUCUACAUCUCCCUGCAUCGCCAUGACGACGGCAACUUCUUCCCGGGGAGUGGGGCUGUGGAUGAGGUAGGGGCUGGCAGCGGUGAGGGCUUCAAUGUCAAUGUGGCCUGGGCUGGAGGUCUGGACCCCCCCAUGGGGGAUCCUGAGUACCUGGCUGCUUUCAGGAUAGUCGUGAUGCCCAUCGCCCGAGAGUUCUCUCCAGACCUAGUCCUGGUGUCUGCUGGAUUUGAUGCUGCUGAGGGUCACCCGGCCCCACUGGGUGGCUACCAUGUUUCUGCCAAAUGUUUUGGAUACAUGACGCAGCAACUGAUGAACCUGGCAGGAGGCGCAGUGGUGCUGGCCUUGGAGGGUGGCCAUGACCUCACAGCCAUCUGUGACGCCUCUGAGGCCUGUGUGGCUGCUCUUCUGGGUAACAGGGUGGAUCCCCUUUCAGAAGAAGGCUGGAAACAGAAACCCAACCUCAAUGCCAUCCGCUCUCUGGAGGCCGUGAUCCGGGUGCACAGUAAAUACUGGGGCUGCAUGCAGCGCCUGGCCUCCUGUCCAGACUCCUGGGUGCCUAGAGUGCCAGGGGCUGACAAAGAAGAAGUGGAGGCAGUGACCGCACUGGCGUCCCUCUCUGUGGGCAUCCUGGCUGAAGAUAGGCCCUCGGAGCAGCUGGUGGAGGAGGAAGAACCUAUGAAUCUCUAAGGCUCUGGAACCAUCUGCCCGCCCACCAUGCCCUUGGGACCUGGUUCUCUUCUAACCCCUGGCAAUAGCCCCCAUUCCUGGGUCUUUAGAGAUCCUGUGGGCAAGUAGUUGGAACCAGAGAACAGCCUGCCUGCUUUGACAGUUAUCCCAGGGAGCGUGAGAAAAUCCCUGGGUCUAGAAUGGGAACUGGAGAGGACCCUGAGAGGAGACGGGCUGGGCGGCGACCCCCACAGGGCUCUCGAGAACAGAUUCUCCCCUCCAGUAUGGGCCCUGGCUGUGGCCCCCAUUCCUCAGGACUGCACAGAGGAGGACUGGCUCCGGCUCCGUCGGGCUCACCCUUAACCACUAUUCCUGGCUCUGCAAACCCCAGACUUUGCACACAGCCUCAGGCUCCACACAGAAAUGUGAACUUGGCCUCAGACAGGCUGGCCCUUCCUAGGCUCUAGGGGCUAGGGGGGAGUGGGGAGCCAAGAGGUCCCAUAUUCCUGAGUGCAGGGGUAGUCCCUCUCACCUGCUUCCUCAGACGACUCUGGAAGCUUCCCUCUACCACUGGGCACUGAGACGAAGCUCCCUGACAGCCGAGACUGGCAGCCCUCCAUCUGGUCCGUACCCUCGCCAGAGGCCCCCCUACAUCAACCUCCUGGCGAUGCCCUGGUGGAGCAGAUGGGUGCUCUGGGAGUCCUGUGCUUCCUGAUCCAAUGGUGCCAAACCCUUCAUCUCCCCAAGAAGCGCAGCAUACCCCUGGGACCCCUCGGCCACUGCCCACUCGGGGAGCCUUCUCUGUUUCUGGGGCCUCCCCCACCAUAGCUCUGAUUCCCACCCCACAUAGGAGUAGCCUGACUGAGGGGGAAGGGGUGGGAGAGAAGAUACAGACAUGGAGGAGGGGAGGCUGCUCUGGCAAAGUCUUCAAGGCUUUUGGGGGUCCAGGCCUGGGGUCAAGAAGGAAAAUGUGUGUGAGCAUGUGUGUGAGUGAGGCGUGUGUGUGAGCGUGUGUGUGAGUGAGGCGUGUGUGUGUGUCUUUCCUAGGACCCACCAUACCCUGUGUAUGUAUGCAUGUUUUUGUAAAAAGGAAGAAAAUGGAAAAAAAUCUGAACAAUAAAUGUUUUAUUUGCUUUAAAA